GUCUCAUUCUAUAGCCCUCAUUCCAGCACAGGAUCUCAGCAAUUUUUCCCUCUUCCCCCCACCCACUCCAGCGCGCAGAGUCCUUUCUUCUCUCUCAUUUACAACUUCUUUUUAAAAGAAAACAUUUUCUAGAAAAAGGGCUUUGCUAAACAGAAAAGAUAUAAAACAAAAGCCACAGCUAUCUAGCAUGGCAUUGUCACCAACUCCCUUUGCAUGGUGAUGCGAUUAAGGUAGCAGCAUUUUUAUUAUUCAGGAAAAGCAGCUGGGGGAUUCAUCAGUUCUGAGGCUUUGUCUUUCUGGGUUAACUGAUGGUCCCAAGCCUCGGUUUGACCUGACCAUGAUGCCCAGGACUGGCACUUUUUCUUUUUUCUCAGCAAACUGUACAAAACCAAAUCUCUUUUUGAUUUUCAAGGAAACUAGGUUCCUGCCAAAUUUUGAAUCUGGACAAUAAACAGACACUUUGUCCUAGCAUCUUUCUGGAAUCAUUUCGGGAUAUUUUCCACAAGCAACACAGAAACAGGAAUGAACCGGCAGCUAGUGAACAUUUUGACAGCCUUGUUUGCAUUUUUCUUAGAGACAAACCACUUCAGGUUUACACCUCCUACUAUGAUUAAGAAAAAAUAUAGGCUGGUUUUUAUUAGAAUCAUCAUCAUCAUCAUCAUCCUCACCACCACCACCAUCAUAAUCAAAUAAUACUUGAUUAAUCAGAUGAAUCUGCAUAUGAGAAUGACGGCUUUCUGCAAAGACCAUGACUCCAGGUCUGGAAAACAACCUUCACAGACCCUAUCUCCUUCAGAUUUCUUGGACAAGUUAAUGGGAAGGACAUCAGGAUAUGAUGCAAGAAUCAGGCCAAAUUUUAAAGGUCCUCCAGUAAACGUUACUUGCAAUAUUUUUAUCAACAGUUUUGGAUCAGUCACAGAAACGACCAUGGACUACCGAGUGAAUAUUUUUCUGAGACAACAGUGGAAUGAUUCACGGCUGGCGUACAGUGAGUACCCAGAUGACUCCCUGGACUUGGACCCAUCCAUGCUAGACUCCAUUUGGAAACCAGAUUUGUUCUUUGCCAAUGAGAAGGGUGCCAACUUCCACGAUGUCACCACUGACAACAAAUUGCUACGGAUUUCGAAAAAUGGCAAAGUGCUCUACAGUAUCAGACUCACCUUGACCUUAUCCUGUCCCAUGGACUUGAAGAACUUUCCGAUGGAUGUCCAGACCUGUACAAUGCAGCUGGAGAGUUUUGGGUACACGAUGAAUGACCUGAUAUUUGAGUGGUUAAGUGAUGGUCCAGUGCAAGUUGCUGAAGGAUUGACCCUGCCCCAGUUUAUUUUGAAAGAAGAGAAGGAACUUGGCUACUGUACAAAGCACUACAACACUGGAAAGUUUACCUGCAUUGAGGUCAAGUUUCAUCUGGAACGCCAAAUGGGAUAUUAUUUGAUCCAGAUGUACAUCCCAAGCCUGCUUAUAGUAAUUUUGUCCUGGGUUUCCUUUUGGAUAAAUAUGGAUGCAGCCCCUGCCAGGGUCGCACUGGGCAUCACCACAGUCUUAACGAUGACCACCCAGAGUUCAGGCUCCAGGGCAUCUCUGCCAAAGGUCUCCUAUGUAAAAGCGAUUGACAUCUGGAUGGCGGUGUGCCUUCUGUUUGUGUUUGCUGCCUUACUGGAAUACGCAGCGGUGAACUUCGUCUCCAGGCAACACAAGGAGUUCCUGCGCCUCCGAAGAAGACAGAAGAGGCAGAAUAAGGAAGAAGACGUUACUCGUGAAAGUCGUUUUAAUUUUAGCGGUUAUGGGAUGGGUCACUGCCUCCAAGUGAAAGAUGGAACAGCUGUCAAGGCCACACCUGCCAACCCACUCCCACAACCGCCAAAAGAUGGAGAUGCUAUCAAGAAGAAGUUUGUGGACCGGGCAAAAAGGAUUGACACGAUAUCUCGAGCUGCCUUCCCAUUGGCCUUCCUCAUUUUCAACAUCUUUUACUGGAUCACAUACAAGAUCAUUCGGCAUGAAGAUGUCCACAAGAAAUAGAUGUGCCCUACAGACCCUGGGACCUUCUUGCCUCAGUGUUGUGCUUGUAAAUACACAGUGAAAUUGUCUUUAUAUCACUUUGACAGAGGAGAAGAUUGAGGGAGGGGGGAGGGAGGGUCAUGGGGGUGGGUUUCCUGGCACCUACAUGAAAAAAAAGACAAGUUAUAUGGGUGAUGAAGAAAACUGCACAAAAUUAAGGGGUUGCAGAAUCACGGGAGCAUAAUAAUUCCCUUCCAUAAUCUUUAGCAUUGUUCUUUCAGUCAGACAUGAUAUGCGCAACAUUCAGACAUGAUAUGCGCAUCAUUCAGACAUGAUAUGCGGGGUCAAGUUCUUAAGGGCUGUUUGCCUUUUGGUCCUUUUGGUUUGGUUUGGCUUUGACUAAUUCUGGUACUGAAAAGUUAGCUAUACACACACACACACACACACACACACACACACACACACACACACACACACACACACACAAACUUCAAAAAUGCUUAACCAUCUGACCAUAGUGACUAGCCUAUAGUGAGUCGAGGACCAAACUUUUUCAGGAAAAUGCUGCCUCGUUUUUAAAACAAGCCUCCUAAGCUAUGUUCUUUACAAUGUCUGUAAUUAGUGUUUCACUUGAGAAAGCCUUUUGUGGGUCGUAAAUUAUUUCUACUUAUCCAGUAAAUAACAAUGACAAAAUAAACACCAAUGACAGAAAAAUUUCUACUUUACUGUCCAUAUAGGUGUGCAUUUUAAUAUUUUUCUUUCCAAGAUAAAAUUUUGAAACUUAAAUUGUGUAUUGUGUAAUUAAUUUGAUAGUGUACCCUCUUAAUAAAUGCCCACUUUAUUUUAUAUCCAAGUUAGUGCAUUAUAUAUAUAUUUUUGCUUUGGCUAUAUUUACACGUGACUUUAAUCGCCCAACUGUGACUAGUCAUUGCAGCUACUCAGCUACAGUAUUUAUGGAGAUGGUGUGUCCUGAACAGUGUAGCUCAGGUCAGCUUGAACUUUCCAUUUCUGCUCUCAUUGUAGGUGUAACUACUAGUCCUAAUGUCAACUGACCCAUGAUUUCUACUGUCAGUCAAUAUAAGUGAACAUUGUUUUAAAUAUCCUUAACUAACUUAAAGAAUUUUAAAAUUGUACUGUGAUUUUCAUAACCCGUUGCCUUUUUGGUACCAGAGCUACGUGGUUUGAAUUCUGGCUACAUGUUUUAAGUAAGAAAAAAAAAGACGUAUUUUUGCUUACUCAGAUAAAAGACAACCUGUAAAAAUAUAAUAAUUAAAUUUUACAUGUGCUGUACAAGGGGUUAUUUUAAAAAGCAUUUGUUCAAUUUCAAUAAAGCUAAGUGUGCCGCAAA